AGAGUCCCUCGGGUCUCAGGUCAUGGCGGUCGCGGGGCCCGCGCCCGGAGCUGGCGCCAGGCCCAGGUUAGAUCUGCAAUUUCUCCAGCGGUUCCUGCAGAUACUGAAGGUUUUGUUUCCUUCUUGGUCAUCACAAAAUGCCUUGAUGUUCCUGACCCUUUUGUGCCUGACCCUACUGGAGCAAUUUGUGAUCUACCAGGUUGGCUUGAUCCCCAGUCAGUACUAUGGGGUCCUGGGAAACAAAGACUUGGAAGGGUUUAAGACUCUGACAUUCCUGGCUGUCAUGCUCAUUGUUCUGAACUCCACGCUGAAGAGCUUUGAUCAGUUCACCUGCAACCUGCUGUAUGUGAGCUGGAGGAAGGACCUCACUGAGCACCUUCACCGCCUCUACUUCCGGGGCCGUGCGUACUACACCCUCAACGUGCUGCGGGAUGACAUCGAUAACCCGGACCAGCGCAUCAGCCAGGACGUGGAGCGAUUCUGCCGGCAGCUCAGCAGCAUGGCCAGCAAGCUCAUCAUCUCCCCGUUCACCCUCGUCUACUACACUUACCAGUGCUUCCAAAGCACAGGCUGGCUCGGGCCUGUGAGCAUCUUCGGGUAUUUCAUCCUGGGGACCGUGGUGAACAAAACUUUGAUGGGCCCCAUUGUGAUGAAGCUGGUGCAUCAGGAGAAGCUGGAGGGAGAUUUUAGGUUCAAGCACAUGCAGAUUCGGGUGAAUGCGGAGCCUGCUGCUUUCUACAGAGCUGGGCAUGUGGAGCACAUGAGGACAGACCGCAGGCUGCAGAGACUCCUUCAGACCCAGAGGGAGCUGAUGUCCAAGGAGCUCUGGCUGUACAUCGGCAUCAACACCUUUGACUAUCUGGGCAGCAUCCUGAGUUACGUUGUCAUCGCAAUCCCCAUUUUCAGCGGGGUCUAUGGAGACCUGAGUCCCGCAGAGCUUAGCACCCUGGUCAGCAAGAAUGCCUUUGUGUGCAUCUACCUCAUCAGCUGCUUCACCCAGCUCAUCGACCUGUCCACGACGCUCUCAGAUGUGGCUGGCUACACGCACAGAAUUGGGCAGCUUCGGGAGACGCUUCUGGACAUGUCCCUGAAGUCACAGGACUGCGAGAUCCUGGGCGAGAGCGAGUGGGGCUUGGACACACCCCCAGGGUGGCCAGCGGCAGAGCCAGCAGACACAGCAUUUCUCCUUGAGCGGGUCUCCAUCUCUGCCCCCUCCUCUGACAAACCCCUAAUCAAGGAUCUGAGCCUAAAGAUCUCCGAGGGACAGAGCCUGCUCAUCACAGGCAACACGGGCACUGGCAAGACCUCCUUGCUCCGGGUUCUGGGUGGCCUCUGGACGAGUACACGGGGCUCAGUGCAGAUGCUGACGGACUUUGGGCCCCAUGGGGUGCUAUUCCUGCCACAAAAGCCAUUCUUCACUGACGGGACCCUUCGGGAGCAGGUGAUAUAUCCCCUGAAGGAGGUCUACCCCGACUCAGGUUCUGCCGAUGAUGAGAGGAUCUUGAGGUUCUUGGAAUUGGCAGGCCUGGUAAGUGGGGAGAGGGACCCUCAGGACCCGAGCCCACCUGGGAGCACCAGCUACAGUCCAACUUGGUGGCAAGGACAGAGGGCCUGGACCAGCAGGUGGACUGGAACUGGUAUGAUGUUCUGUCCCCGGGGGAGAUGCAACGGCUCUCCUUUGCCCGACUCUUCUACCUGCAGCCGAAGUACGCAGUGCUUGAUGAAGCCACCAGUGCCCUGACAGAGGAAGUGGAGAGCGAGCUCUAUCGCAUCGGCCAGCAGCUGGGGAUGACGUUCAUCAGUGUGGGACAUCGGCAGAGCCUUGAGAAGGUACCCGUGCUCACAAGGAUGGCCUGAGGAGGAGAAAGAACCCAAAGGCUCAGCCUGGCCAGGGCCAGAGGCCCCUCAAAACGGGGAGUAGCAGUAGCAGAGAGAACCGAGUGGCCUCCUCUGCCAGCGGCCAGGGCAGCCUGAUCUCCAUGUGGUGGUGGUCUCUUGUAGUUUCAUUCCUUGGUUCUGAAACUCUGUGGAGGAGGAAGAUGGGAGCUGAUGAGAAUCAAAGUGGAAUGAAGCUCUGGCUUUUGGAAGGAGAGCCACACUGUGGCGGGUCGGCGGCCCUCAGGAGAGACCAGGAGGACUGACAGCGAAGAUCGAGCUCAGGUUCGCCACAUAGAUCCCGUGCAGGAGCCACAUGGGUCCUGUGCAGGACCCCUAGCAGUGGUGGGCUGAGCCCAGGUCUAGGUUUCUGUGGGGGACACUGAAUCUCCCAGUGUUCAGUCUCCCAGGACUCUGCUGCCUCAGCCAGAGCCUCCAUAUGCUUGAAGUGCUGAUUACCUACAAAUGAUUUCAGAUCAUGUUUGCUAAAGAGAAAUCUGGAAGUGUGAGAUCUGUAAGAAAUGAAAGAAAUGACUCUUGGAGUCAAGAGAUCUGGAAAUCUUUUAAUCAGUUAAAUUGUGCAGCAAUAGAUUUUUAACUUUAACUGACCAUUUAAGUUUUUUAAUAAGUUUUUUACAAAGAAAAGUUAAACAUUAAAAAGAAUUACAGCUUUCUGUCUUCUCUAUCAUGGAAUGAUCUUUUUUAUUGAAUCUCCAGAUUUGUAUUUGACAGCUUGGUGGGAAGGGAAGCACACUCUGCUGUUCUGGAAUCUUAUGCCCAGGGUUUUUCACUUCUCCCCACAUCUCCCUUUCCACUUGCCAGUGUUGUGUAGUUAGAACCUGAACCACUAACUUCCAGGGGCCUUUGGUCUGCCCUACCUUAACCCAAAUGAAAGUAAAUCCCUUUCCCCUUAGCCAAAAUAAGGUUGGGUUUUCUAAAAAAAUAGUCUAUAUUAGGGAACAACAACAGCAAAUUAGACAAAACCCAGAAAGCACAAAGCAUGAGGUGGAGUUACUGUGCCCAAAGUCCUCACUCAGACCAGUGCCCCUCCAGUUCAGUUGUCUAUGUAUUACCUUCCUUACCUUCAUAAUUUUUGCCAGGCUUCUGUACUUCUAGUACUUGAGUUACUUAAUAUUUUUAAAAACAAACCUUUUAAGUUUAAAUGGAUUUUUAAGUGAAAUUUUACACUUAACAUAGAUGGAAAGUAACUAAAAAUAAAUACAAGAAAAACCAUCGGUGUUAUUAACUUACGGCUAGAUGCUGUUGCCUGCAUAGACUCUGGGCCUGAGGCUUGUUCAUUUUGUAAAAAAGAGAGGUGAGGAGUUAGACGGACUGGCACUCAACUGAGAUUUUUCUCCUUAAUAAAAUCAGAAAGAUGGAGUGAGAA